CCCGCCUCAGCCUCCCAAAGUGCUGGGAUUACAGGUGUGAGCCACUGCGCCCGUCCUGACUCAUGCAACUUCUGCUUCAGCCAUCCAGGGGUCUUUAACCAGAAGAGAGAGGAGAGCCUCAGGAGUUAGGACCAGAAGAAGCCAGGGAAGCAGUGCAAUGGCUUCAAAAAUCUUGCUUAACGUACAAGAGGAGGUGACCUGUCCCAUCUGCCUGGAGCUGUUGACAGAACCCUUGAGUCUAGACUGUGGCCACAGCCUCUGCCGAGCCUGCAUCACUGUGAGCAACAAGGAGGCAGUGACCAGCAUGGGAGGAAAAAGCAGCUGUCCUGUGUGUGGUAUCAGUUACUCAUUUGAACAUCUACAGGCUAAUCAGCAUCUGGCCAACAUAGUGGAGAGACUCAAGGAGGUCAAGUUGAGCCCAGACAAUGGGAAGAAGAGAGAUCUCUGUGAUCAUCAUGGAGAGAAACUCCUACUCUUCUGUAAGGAGGAUAGGAAAGUCAUUUGCUGGCUUUGUGAGCGGUCUCAGGAGCACCGUGGUCACCACACAGUCCUCACGGAGGAAGUAUUCAAGGAAUGUCAGGAGAAACUCCAGGCAGUCCUCAAGAGGCUGAAGAAGGAAGAGGAGGAAGCUGAGAAGCUGGAAGCUGACAUCAGAGAAGAGAAAACUUCCUGGAAGUAUCAGGUACAAACUGAGAGACAAAGGAUACAAACAGAAUUUGAUCAGCUUAGAAGCAUCCUAAAUAAUGAGGAGCAGAGAGAGCUGCAAAGAUUGGAAGAAGAAGAAAAGAAGACGCUGGAUAAGUUUGCAGAGGCUGAGGAUGAGCUAGUUCAGCAGAAGCAGUUGGUGAGAGAGCUCAUCUCAGAUGUGGAGUGUCGGAGUCAGUGGUCAACAAUGGAGCUGCUGCAGGACAUGAGUGGAAUCAUGAAAUGGAGUGAGAUCUGGAGGCUGAAAAAGCCAAAAAUGGUUUCCAAGAAACUGAAGACUGUAUUCCAUGCUCCAGAUCUGAGUAGGAUGCUGCAAAUGUUUAGAGAACUGACAGCUGUCCGGUGCUACUGGGUGGAUGUCACACUGAAUUCAGUCAACCUAAAUUUGAAUCUUGUCCUUUCAGAAGAUCAGAGACAAGUGAUAUCUGUGCCAAUUUGGCCUUUUCAGUGUUAUAAUUAUGGUGUCUUGGGAUCCCAAUAUUUCUCCUCUGGGAAACAUUACUGGGAAGUGGACGUGUCCAAGAAAACUGCCUGGAUCCUGGGGGUAUACUGUAGAACAUAUUCCCGCCAUAUGAAGUAUGUUGUUAGAAGAUGUGCAAAUCGUCAAAAUCUUUACACCAAAUACAGACCUCUAUUUGGCUACUGGGUUAUAGGGUUACAGAAUAAAUGUAAGUAUGGUGUCUUUGAAGAGUCUUUGUCCUCUGAUCCCGAGGUUUUGACUCUCUCCAUGGCUGUGCCUCCCUGCCGUGUUGGGGUUUUCCUCGACUAUGAAGCAGGCAUUGUCUCAUUUUUCAAUGUCACAAGCCAUGGCUCCCUCAUUUACAAGUUCUCUAAAUGUUGCUUUUCUCAGCCUGUUUAUCCAUAUUUCAAUCCUUGGAACUGUCCAGCUCCCAUGACUCUAUGCCCACCAAGCUCUUGAAUUUUCUCAUUUCUUCACCUACAACCCUUUGUCUUGACUUAUCUCCUGCAACUGACUCAUCUGCAACAUUCACACCAUUGCUUCCUUGUGGUUUCCCUUCUUUAGAACUUUUACUCAUCCUUGAGAUGUAUGGUGUAUUUGGCUUGAGUUAUGAGAGAUGCUUAUUUAUUCAUUUACUCUUUUUCAUAUUUUCAGAGAAAGUUACCUAAUCCCUCCUAAAGACACAGCAGUAUGGGUAUAACAUCCUUGCCUUCCCAUUUAUCCAUGUUUCACUUUAUCACUGAUAUGAAGAGGCCCAAAGCCUGUUAGCCACCAUCCAUGCUACCUAGGUAGUCCAUAGGAACCACCCCCAUGACCACCACCAACAUCAACUAAAGGUUCUUGGAGGGUAUGUCAGUGUGUUGCUCAGGAUACCCCAGGUACAUCAAGGAAUCAAGGAGAGGAAAAUAUGAGCAAUAUGUGUAUUCAGAGUGAAGAUUUUAUGUCCAGAGUAUUUGAGCUCAAACCUUGCCUGUUGUUUUCUAAUCAUGAUGAAUACUUUCUCAGUUUCUUUUUCCUGAAAUAUAAAUUGGGAUUUAAGACUGUACCUAACUAUUAAGAUCACUGUGUAAAACUAAGUGUCUCUAAAUGUAAUGCAUCGAUUUAGUGUCUGGAACAUAAUAAAUAUUUGCUCUCAUGAUUGCUAAAAA